GAUUAUGCUGGCAUCCAGGGCUUGCAAGUGGCAGCUUCAGCACCCAGGGCUGUGGUAGGUCACAGUCUCUGGGCGGGUCUCAGUGUCCAACACUGUAGCUGGUGCCUGCCAGGUUCCCAGUGGCUGGGGUCACCAGGUCUGAAGAGAGAUGUGCUGGCUGCGGGCAUGGGGCCAGAUCCUCCUGCCAGUUUUCCUCUCCCUCUUUCUCAUCCAAUUGCUUAUCAGCUUCUCAGAGAAUGGUUUUAUCCACAGCCCCAGGAACAAUCAGAAACCAAGAGAUGGGAAUGAAGAGGAAUGUGCUGUAAAGAAGAGUUGUCAAUUGUGCACAGAAGAUAAGAAAUGUGUUUGGUGUAGUGAAGAAAAAGCAUGCAAAAAAUACUGUUUUCCCUAUUUCGGUUGUCGAUUCAGUUCUAUAUAUUGGUUAAACUGUAAAGUUGACAUGUUUGGAAUCAUGAUGCUUCUACUCAUUGCAGUAUUAAUUACAGGAUUCGUUUGGUACUGCUGCGCCUAUCACUUUUACCUGCAGGAUUUGAACAGAAAUCGUGUCUAUUUUUAUGGAAGACGAGAAACAGUUCCUAUUCACGACCGCAGUGCUACUGUAUAUGAUGAAUAGAUAAUUGAAAAGAGAUCCUCCAGAAAGAGCAGAAGGAAGUUUCUUCAAUGGCUUCCUUCAGGAUUUUAAUCAUCCUUACAGCCUCUUUGAGAAUGAUUGAACUUCCAAAUUCCCUGAAGUUAAAAUUUUAAAUUCUAUUAAACAUUUUUUCGAGUAUUUCAUUACUUUUA